GAGUUAGCUAGAGCUGUUGCCAUGACAAGCAUUUUCUUAAGAAAGCUCUGCUGUUGAGAUCGUCCAAAGCUGGGGGCUGGGAGGGGGGGCACGAACUUCGUGGGGCACCAUCCCUCCGAAGAGAGCAAGAUCAGAGACACCCGCCCAGCUCUCCUGCACCCUUUUUCUUUCAGGAACCUGAGAGGUCCUUCCCAUUGGAGGGGCAGGGGGAGGAGACCCAGCCCACUCCCCGGCCUUAGCCAGAAAGGCAAGAGAGCAAAGCCAGCGUCUCUAGCUUGGUUGCCACACUGGGGAGACUGGUGGGUGGUCACCCCACCCUACCCUCAUCCAUGGAAACCCGGAGGGAGAGUCCCGCCUGAAGAAACCUGGAUCUUUGCUAGAAAGAGAGAGAUCCAGUUGUCAUCGGUAUCCAGGAAGCUCUCCUCUUCCUCCUCCUGACGUCUACUACUACAGUUGCUGGUUGUUGCUAAGGUUGCUGCCAUGGUAACAUGCACAUCCUGUUUACACCUUCAUCUGGGCAAGUUGGUCUAAGCUAGGAACCUACCUACCCUGGACAACUACUAUCAUCACCACCUGGGGACACCAAUCAUCGUGACACGGAGUCCACCUUCCACUCAGUUCCCCCAUCCUCUUCCUCCUCUCGCUGCCAGACUUCAUACGGAAGAAAGGAUCUAGACUUCGGACGGCUACUCGGGAGCUUAUUGCACAAGAUAUAUUCAAUCUAUUCCCUCACUGGGCCCCCAGAGAAGCAAGAAGUAGGAAGAAGUUGAGACAGGGAGGCAGGAGACACUGGUCAGUUGAAGGGAAACGCUACAUCUUCUCUGGUUGAGGGGCUUGGUAACAGCAGGCAAAAUGACGAACCCAUCAGACCGUGUCUUGCCUGCCAACUCGAUGGCCGAGAGCCGUGAAGGGGACUUUGGCUGCACAGUAAUGGAACUGAGGAAGCUCAUGGAGCUGCGUUCAAGGGAUGCACUGACCCAGAUUAAUGUCCACUAUGGAGGUGUACAGAAUCUCUGCAGUAGACUGAAAACCUCCCCUGUGGAAGGUCUGUCUGGGAACCCUGCAGAUCUGGAGAAACGUAGGCAGGUGUUUGGACACAACGUGAUCCCCCCCAAAAAGCCCAAGACUUUCUUAGAAUUAGUGUGGGAAGCUCUUCAAGAUGUCACGCUUAUCAUCCUGGAGAUUGCAGCCAUCAUCUCCCUGGUCCUGUCCUUUUAUCGCCCUGCUGGUGAAGAAAAUGAACUGUGUGGUCAAGUCGCAACUACCCCAGAAGAUGAAAAUGAGGCACAAGCUGGCUGGAUUGAGGGGGCAGCCAUCCUUUUCUCAGUGAUCAUCGUGGUGUUAGUGACUGCCUUUAAUGAUUGGAGCAAAGAGAAGCAAUUCCGGGGGCUGCAGUGCCGCAUUGAACAGGAGCAAAAGUUCUCCAUCAUCCGAAACGGUCAACUCAUCCAGCUCCCUGUGGCUGAGAUUGUGGUUGGUGAUAUUGCCCAAGUCAAAUACGGUGAUCUGCUGCCUGCAGAUGGAAUCCUGAUCCAAGGGAAUGAUCUGAAGAUUGAUGAGAGCUCUCUGACAGGGGAAUCUGACCAUGUCAAGAAGUCCCUGGACAAAGACCCCAUGUUGCUCUCAGGGACCCAUGUCAUGGAAGGUUCUGGCCGGAUGGUGGUGACAGCUGUUGGUGUCAACUCUCAGACUGGAAUCAUCCUUACUCUCUUGGGGGUCAAUGAGGAUGACGAAGGGGAGAAAAAGAAGAAAGGUAAAAAACAAGGAGUCCCUGAAAAUCGCAACAAAGCAAAGACCCAAGACGGAGUGGCCCUGGAAAUCCAGCCACUCAACAGCCAGGAGGGAAUCGACAAUGAGGAAAAGGACAAGAAGGCAGUCAAGGUGCCUAAAAAGGAGAAGUCAGUGCUGCAGGGCAAGCUGACUCGCCUGGCUGUUCAGAUUGGGAAAGCCGGUCUGCUCAUGUCUGCUCUCACGGUUUUCAUCCUGAUUCUAUACUUUGUGAUUGACAACUUUGUGAUAAAUCGCAGACCAUGGCUCCCUGAGUGUACUCCCAUCUACAUCCAGUACUUUGUCAAGUUCUUCAUCAUCGGCAUCACUGUACUGGUGGUGGCUGUGCCAGAGGGGCUGCCUCUGGCUGUCACCAUCUCACUGGCCUACUCUGUGAAGAAAAUGAUGAAAGACAAUAACCUAGUACGGCACUUGGAUGCUUGUGAGACCAUGGGCAACGCCACCGCCAUCUGCUCUGAUAAGACAGGCACGUUGACCAUGAACCGCAUGACUGUGGUACAAGCUUAUAUUGGGGGCAUCCAUUACCGUCAAAUCCCAAGCCCUGAUGUCUUCCUGCCCAAAGUCCUGGACCUCAUUGUCAAUGGCAUUUCUAUCAACAGUGCUUAUACCUCCAAGAUUCUGCCUCCAGAGAAGGAGGGAGGCCUGCCUCGGCAGGUGGGCAACAAGACCGAGUGUGCUCUGCUAGGCUUUGUCACAGAUCUGAAGCAGGAUUAUCAGGCUGUGCGUAAUGAAGUGCCCGAGGAGAAGCUCUACAAGGUGUACACCUUUAACUCAGUGCGCAAGUCAAUGAGCACCGUCAUCAGGAAUCCCAACGGUGGCUUCCGUAUGUACAGCAAGGGCGCCUCUGAGAUCAUCUUGCGCAAGUGUAAUCGAAUCCUGGACCGGAAAGGGGAAGCAGUGCCAUUCAAGAAUAAAGACAGAGAUGAUAUGGUACGCACUGUCAUCGAGCCCAUGGCCUGUGAUGGACUCCGGACUAUCUGCAUAGCUUACCGGGACUUCGAUGACACAGAGCCCUCUUGGGACAAUGAGAAUGAGAUCCUCACCGAACUGACCUGUAUCGCGGUGGUGGGCAUUGAGGACCCUGUGCGCCCAGAGGUGCCAGAUGCUAUUGCCAAAUGCAAACAAGCUGGCAUUACUGUCAGAAUGGUGACAGGUGACAACAUCAACACAGCCCGGGCCAUUGCCACCAAAUGUGGCAUUCUGACACCUGGGGAUGACUUCCUGUGCUUAGAAGGCAAAGAAUUCAACCGGCUCAUCCGCAACGAGAAAGGCGAGGUAGAGCAAGAAAAGCUGGACAAGAUCUGGCCUAAGCUUCGGGUCCUGGCGCGAUCUUCUCCCACUGACAAGCACACCCUGGUGAAAGGCAUAAUUGACAGCACUGUUGGGGAACACCGGCAGGUCGUGGCUGUCACUGGUGAUGGCACAAAUGACGGGCCUGCUCUGAAGAAAGCGGAUGUUGGUUUUGCCAUGGGCAUCGCAGGCACAGAUGUAGCAAAGGAGGCUUCAGACAUCAUCCUAACAGAUGACAACUUCACCAGCAUUGUGAAGGCAGUGAUGUGGGGACGAAAUGUCUAUGACAGCAUCUCCAAGUUCCUGCAGUUCCAGCUCACUGUCAAUGUGGUGGCCGUGAUUGUAGCCUUCACUGGAGCCUGUAUCACUCAGGAUUCCCCAUUGAAAGCUGUGCAGAUGUUGUGGGUUAAUCUGAUCAUGGACACUUUUGCUUCAUUGGCCCUGGCCACAGAGCCCCCUACGGAAUCUCUGUUGAAGCGGCGCCCCUAUGGCCGAAAUAAGCCUCUGAUCUCACGCACUAUGAUGAAGAACAUCUUGGGCCAUGCAUUCUAUCAGCUCAUUGUCAUCUUUAUCCUUGUCUUUGCGGGUGAGAAAUUCUUUGAUAUUGAUAGUGGGAGGAAGGCACCUCUACAUUCACCACCCAGCCAGCACUAUACCAUUGUUUUUAACACCUUCGUGCUGAUGCAGCUCUUCAAUGAAAUCAACUCCCGAAAGAUCCAUGGAGAGAAGAACGUCUUUUCAGGCAUCUACCGCAACAUUAUCUUCUGCUCUGUAGUCUUGGGCACAUUCAUCUGCCAGAUUUUCAUCGUGGAAUUUGGGGGUAAACCCUUCAGUUGUACAAGCCUCAGCCUGUCUCAGUGGCUGUGGUGUCUCUUCAUUGGGAUUGGAGAACUUCUGUGGGGCCAGUUCAUCUCCGCAAUACCUACCCGAUCCCUGAAGUUCCUGAAGGAGGCUGGGCAUGGCACCACCAAAGAGGAGAUCACCAAGGAUGCCGAGGGACUGGAUGAGAUUGACCAUGCUGAGAUGGAGCUGCGCCGAGGCCAGAUCCUCUGGUUCCGGGGCCUGAACCGUAUCCAGACUCAGAUCGACGUAAUUAACACAUUCCAGACGGGAGCCUCUUUUAAGGGAGUCCUAAGGCGACAGAACAUGGGUCAACACCUUGAUGUAAAACUUGUUCCUAGUUCAUCCUAUGUAGCAGUUGCACCAGUCAAAUCUUCCCCCACCACUUCUGUUCCUGCUGUUUCAUCUCCUCCUAUGGGCAAUCAAAGUGGUCAAAGCGUUCCAUAGUUCCCUCCACGAAAGCAUUCAGAAACCCUACAACCAAAAGUCCAUCCACAGCUUCAUGACCCACCCUGAAUUCGCCAUAGAGGAGGAGUUGCCACGAACACCACUCCUGGAUGAGGAAGAGGAGGAAAAUCCUGACAAGGCUUCUAAGUUUGGGACUAGGGUGCUCCUGUUGGAUGGUGAGGUCACUCCAUAUGCCAAUACAAACAACAAUGCGGUGGAUUGCAACCAAGUGCAGCUCCCCCAGUCGGACAGCUCUCUACAGAGCCUAGAGACAUCAGUUUGAAUUUUCUUUCUCUGACUCUCAUCCCUAUUUUACCUAUUUCCAUUUUCGUCUAUCCCAUCUAUGAGGUGAUGAUGGGACUUUUCAUUGUCACGUCAGCUGCUGUGUUAACAGCAGUGUGUGUGAAGUGAACCUCUACCUGACCAUGAAGAGGCAAGAGCACAGACUUACAAGGAUUUCAACUUAAGCUUGACUUGGGGUUUGUAGCGGGACCCAGUCAAACCCCAUUCAGGUCAUGGUAGAAUCUACUCCUUGGUAGUCACUUGUCAUUUUUAAAGAAAUGAUGACAAUCCUCUUGGCAUCACCCCACCCCACAUUCUCCCCGAUGUUCCUCUCCUGAAUUCUGGAUUUUGUCCUACAAGUCUGUGCCAUUUAUAAGCUAAGUUGAGGGUUCAGAGGGAGACAAAUAUCCCCAAGUGAAAUAUGUUGCGGUAGAGAUGGAAUGUAUAAAAUCCGCCAGUAGUGUGAUUGUUUUUCAAUUUUUCCCACUUUGAAAACUUACACCUAAAGGCCUGUAGGCCUCUAACUCUUUCUGCCCUUUCAUUCAAACCUCUCCAAAGUUCUUUGUCUUUUGUCUUCCCUUCCUUUCCUUUUUUUUUUUUUUUUUUAUGAUGAUUAAGAAAAUGGAAAGGAUAUGGAUGAAUUGUGUAAACUUAGAUCCUUCUCCCUUUUGGCCCAAAAGAACCCUUGAUUUAGUUCCAGAAUCCAACCAGUUUCUUUGUUAAAAGGGUCCUUUUGAAGCAAUUAAGUGCUGGUAAGAAUAUUUCUCUGUUGUUGCCAGGUUACCUUCUGCUUUUAAAUUGCCAUCUUGUAAAGUGUAUGUGGUUCUUAAGUGCCAGGGAGAUCAGCCUUGCCCAUGAAGGUUGCAUAUGUGUGGUAUACAGUUUUUACCUGAAAGCCUGAGCUUUCUCUUAUUCCUAAAGUGGUGGCAAAAGAAUGAACUGGGUAUGACCCUGCCCCCUUACUGGGCUUGGAUAUUGAGGACCAGACGCUGCCAAAUCUAGGACAAGACAGACCAUCAAAGCAGACUUUUGUGGGCUCCUCUUUGGGGUGACCACUGCUUUCAAAGCCAUCUGCCAAGGCUCUCCAGGGCAGGACCUGACUGGUGGGGAAUGAGUGUUCAGAAGCCUUGGGAGAGGCCAAAGAGCCAUUCUAGCAUGAUCUGAGAAAACCUUCCUGCAGAGGCCAGAAACCUUGAGCUUAGGUGCCUGGGGACCAGCUUCGACAUUCUCUCCAGUUUCUGAUUCUAAUUUUUGCCACGUGUCACAACUUUUCCAGUCUCUGAGAAGGUCCCAGCCUUUCUCAAAUAUUCUGAUUUUGAAAAUAUGUAUCCAAAGUGGGAGGCCCCUGUGACAUUUUGCCAACUUAAACGAGAAAAAGACCCCCCGCACCCGGCACACUCCCCCUUCCUCCAGCCCCGCUUCAGCCACAUGCUCCAGCUGCUGCCCAGUAAAGCCCUGUGCCUUUUUUUCCCCUGAAUACUGCCCAAAGCAUCCCCUUCCCAUCUGCCUCUCAGGAGUUGGGGACUUUGCUAGGAGAUUUUUUAAGUGUUCCUUACUGGGACAACGUGGAGCCACGUUUGCAGGAGCUCCAUUUGUAUCCCUGCUGGUGUUGACUUCUGUGUAGGGGCCAGUUCAUGUCCCUGACUCUCACCUCCCAUUAGAUAAAUGAAGCCCACCCCCCUUUCUAGAGUGAUGAGAGUCAAGAAGAGGGGAUGUAUGAACGGCCAAAUUCCCAUGUGAGAGGAAGAUGACCUGAUCCACCUAGCCUUUUCUUCUGGAUCUGUCCUCCCUCACCCCUUUCACCUGAGCUGUCCACAGUAGGAAACAUAAAGAAACAAUGUCCCCUACAUAUCCCCAUGACUACAUAAUCCAUCAUCGUAGGAAAUAGGAAAGCAAAUUUGAUUUUGGUUUUGUAAAACGUACAUGCUUCAAUAAUUCUUUUUUGUGUCUUAAAUACUCAUAGGGGAAAAAAACAGCUCACCCAAGGUGUUAGGUUUCACAUAUAUAUUCAUCAACUAUUUUAGAAGAUUUAAUUCUAUCAAAUCUUGUAUUACCUCAGAUCAUUUUAAAUAGCAAGCCAAUAACGAGCUUUGAAGGCUAUUUUACCAUUCCUGUUCACAAAAGGUUCUCAUGGUGCCUGACAGGUUACCCUUGAGGGCUUGUGUCUACUUUUUAAAAGUCAAUGGUUUUUUUUCUUGUGUUCUAGUUUCCAUAAUAGGAGAGAAAAUAUAGAAAUAUAUGCAAAAAUUAUAGUUUUCUUUAGAUCAGAAACUGAUAUUUUUGGGUCAGCCAUAUGUAUUUUGUUUAAAGGAUUUAAAAUAAAGUGCCGUCAUGUAGCCCUGUGGAAGGGAGCACAUAACCAGCUGUUUGGCAUGACAGGUGACUUAGUAUAUUUGUAAUUGGUUUUAAAACCAAUACACCAUACUUUCUUUCUGCAAACAGCCAUCUUUAUACUUAGGGAAGAAAAAUUGUUGGGUUCUAGACUUUUUUAAUAUAAAUUUUGUUGAUAUGGAAUUAGGUAAGUUUAAGUGUCUAUGUGCAUAUGUUUUUUAUAUAAGUUUUUUCUAUUCAGUUUCACUGAUCCAACUGGCAGUGGGUAAAUAUGGCAUAAGUUAAUAACACUUUUCCCCAAAAUGGUGCUUUGGAUUUGAAAAGGGUCUGAUGGGGAGAAGGAGAACGUAUCAUCCUAGCUUCCUCUCUUAAUAAACCUAGAAAAACGGGUAGUAAACUGUGGAUAGUCAGGAAAACACCCAGCAAGGGACACAGCUGUCAGGAAAUGAAUCUUCCCCCCAACCCCCACCAUGCAGAUGGAUAGACAGAAUCUUUCCUGACUAGUCAUUAGGAUCAGGGGCCUCUGUUGGAUUUGUGUUUCUUGAAGAAUAGCUGGCAGAGUGGUAUAAAAGACACGAAUAUCUCCUGGUCUAUAAGGAUACUCUGAUUUGGGGUUUGCAUUUUUCAUGGUUUUUAUUUCCUGUUCCCCCUGGAGUUUUCCAUUAGUGAGUUUUUGUGCAAGGAUCUUAUUUGUGAUGCCUUCCCUCCCCUAGAAAGAUUUUGUGCAAUAUAUUAAAUGGGGACAGAAUUCUAAAUGGAUAAAACAAUGGCUGGUUCUAGCCCUGAGUGACAGUCUUAAGGCUAGAUCCUUCCCAUAGUAUCAUCUGUCCUCUGGAAUGACUCUCCUGUCCCUAAAGGGGUUAAGAGAGAGAUCACCUAGAAAUCCCUCUGGACACUUGUGGGUUCUUUAGGGUUUGAGUUUCUUCUUCCCCUUGAGCUUCAGAGAGGAGAGUUGGCAUGGUUAAAUCUGAAUGGUUACCUCACUGCUGAAAACCCAGAGGGGCGUGGCACACUCGCUUGUGUGGAAAAGCCUCUAAAUGCAUCCCUUCCUUUCUUUCCUGCUUCCUUUGCCUUACAAUUGAAGCAGCCCGUGGUACCAUCACAGUAUGCAGAGACUUCCUCACCUUUCAUAUCUAGGGACCACCCCCGAUGCAUUGGUGAGGGUGGGCACUUAUAAAUGCCUGCUAUUGUUAAGCCAUUCCAGCCUCUUCCUCUGAAUAGACCAGACGCCCUUUCACUUAGUUCAGUGCCAGUCCUUUUGCCUUCCCAACCCUGCUGUUAGGCCUGCUGUUCCCUUUGCUCUUGAUUAGGAGAGAUGGAAGGAGAUGAGCUCCCAUAACUGAAUUGGCCUUUGGUUCAUGUUUUCUCCCCAUAUGUAUAUAUGCCAUAUGUGAAUAUGCCAUAUAUAUGUGCCAACAAAUCUAUCUACGUUGUUCUUUUCAAAUUAGCACGCAGAUAGGAAUUUUGAGUUUCUUCUUCUUUUAGUAACUAGUAUAACAAGCACUGGUAUUUUUGUACAAAAAAGAAAAACAAAAGAUUGACUAUUGUGGUCUGCAUGACAUAAACAAACAAAUGGUGAUAUCAAAGCAACGUAUACCCCAGUCCAGUGUGUGUUGCCAUAAUUUGCAAUUCAGCUUAACAGUGCACCCAAUCUAUAUUUGCAUUUUGAUAUUAUUUAAGCUCUAUGUACAAGGUUUUGCAUGUAUUUAUAUGGUUCUUAGGGAAAAAAAAUGCUAUAAACUGCAAAUCUGAAAUUCAAAUGUGUUGUUCCACUGAGACCAGAAGAAGAAGAGGAGUUUUAAAAGGGAUAAUUUGUUGGAGCCAAUAAAGCUUUUUGCUGAUGAACAGAAACCAAUACUGCUGUGCACUGAGAAUAAAAACUCAUGCCCACUUGUAA